UUGGCUGGGAUUGACCUUUCUCCCCUAACAGAUUGGAAACUCGUAAUUUCCCGCUUUUUGGUGAAACUCGUUGACAGACACCAUCUGCUCGCUACUACCAGGCUGUUGAAAGCAGAUGGUGGCUGAGGUUUCUCCAAAGCUGGCUGCCUCCCCUAUGAAGAAGCCCUUUGGCUUCAGGGGCAAGAUGGGCAAGUGGUGCUGCUGCUGCUUCCCCUGCUGCAGGGGAAGCGGCAAGAACAACAUGGGUGCUUGGAGAGACCACGACGACAGCGCCUUCACGGAGCCAAGGUAUCACGUCCGUCGAGAAGAUCUGGGCAAGCUCCACAGAGCUGCCUGGUGGGGUGAAGUCCCCAGAGCGGAUCUCAUCGUCAUGCUCAGGGGCCCUGGCAUUAACAAAAGGGACAAGAAGAAGAGGACUGCUCUACACUUGGCCUGUGCCAAUGGCAAUUCAGAAGUAGUAAGUCUUCUGCUGGACAGACAAUGUCAACUUCAUGUCUUUGACAGCAAAAAGAGGACAGCUCUGAUAAAGGCCGUACAAUGCCAGGAGGAUGAAUGUGCGUUAAUGUUGCUACAACAUGGCACUGAUCCAAAUCUUCCAGAUAUGUAUGGGAAUACUGCUCUACACUAUGCAGUCUACAAUGAAGAUAAAUUAAUGGCCAAAACACUGCUUUUAUACGGUGCUGACAUUGAAUCAAAAAACAAGGGUGGCCUCACACCACUUUUGCUUGCUGUACAUGGACAAAAACAGCGAAUGGUGAAAUUUUUAAUCAAGAAAAAAGCUAAUUUAAAUGCACUUGAUAGGUUUGGAAGAACUGCCCUCAUACUUGCUGUACGUUGUGGAUCAGCAAGUAUAGUUAGUCUUCUACUUCAGCAAAAUAUUGAUGUAUUUUCUCAAGAUGUAUUUGGACAAACUGCUGAAGAUUAUGCAGUUUCUAGUCAUCAUAGUAUAAUUUGCCAAUUACUUUCUGACUACAAAGAAAACCAGAUGCCAAACAACUCUUCUGGAAAUAGCAAUCCAGAACAAGACUUAAAGCUGACAUCAGAGGAAGAGCCACAAAGGCUUAAAGGAAGUGAAAAUAGUCAGCAUGAGAAAGUGACUCAAGAACCAGACAUAAAUAAGGAUUGCGAUAGAGAGGUUGAAGAAGAAAUGCAGAAGCAUGGAAGUAAUAAUGUGGGAUUAUCAGAAAACCUGACUGAUGGUGCUGCUGCUGGCAAUGGUGAUGGUGGAUUAGUUCCACAAAGAAAGAGCAGAAAGCAUGAAAAUCAGCAAUUUCCUAACACAGAGAUUGAAGAGUAUCACAGUGAAGAACAAAAUGAUACCCGGAAGCAACUUUCCAAGGAACAGAAUGCUAGAAUAUUACAAGAUGAGAUUCUGACUACUAAACAGAAGCAGAUAGAAGUGGCCGAAAAAAAAAUGAAUUUUGAGAUUUCUCUUAGCCAUAAGGAAGAAAAAGAACUCUUGCAUGAAAAUAGCAUGAUGCAGGAAGAAAUUGCCAUGCUAAGAAUAGAACUAGACACAAUAAAACAUCAGAACCAGCUAAGGGAAAAGAAAUAUCUGGAGUACAUUAAAAGUGUGAAAGAAAAGAAUGAUAAUCUUCUAAAGGCUAUACAAUUGAAUGAGGAAGCACUAACAAAAGCAGUAGUUCAGUACAGUGGACAGCUUAGCAUUUUGACAACUGAGAAUAAAAUGCUCAGUUUUGAACUGCAGAAUGUAAGACACAACAAUGAAACACUGGAAAUGGAAAUUCAAUCAUGUCAUUUUAGACUGGCUACUGCUCUACAUGAUUGUGACUGAAGUCAGAUAGCAGAAAGAGACUUCUUUCCAGAGAACAAGACAUGAACAGGUUUAUUUACAGGAGACAAUGAAUUCUCAUAUAUCUAACCUAAAAGGUAACAGUGAGAUUCUUUCUGAGCAACUCUAAUGCUAACAGUAAAAUUAACAGCCUGAAAAUUAAGGUCCAUCACACAAGAUAAACUCUGAGAGAAAAGACGGGGCAGGCCACCAUUUUUCCUUUUUGGGCAACUUAGUCAUUCCAGCCUGCAGGCUUUGGAGAGUACAAACCGACCAGGGGAAGAAGACAUCCUGCAGCACAGCACAGCUGCUUUAUCAAAUCAUGGCCAGACUGCUUCUGUAAGCAGGCCCCUGAUCCUGUUUCUCCUCACUGGAAAGGACCUCCCAGCUGAGGCCUCCAGCUACCCCCACCAGUGUUCCCUGGCCAACAGAGAUUUAAAUCCCCCCUGGGACAGAGCACCCAGAGAGAGGGGUGGGUCACCACCUUUGCUGUUUGGGCGACUAGCCAUUCAGGCCUGCAGACUUUGGAGAGCCCAAGCUGACCAGGGGUGGAAGUGGUACCUCAGCACAGCACAGCUGCCCUAUGAAAAUGUGACCAGACUCUUUUUUAAGUCAGUCCCUGACCACAUUUGUUAUCACUGAGUGGAGUCUUUCAACCAGGGUCUCUGGCUACCUUCAGUGCUGUUCUCUGGCUGACAGAGGUUUCAGGCCUUCCUGAGUCAGAGCUCCCAGGGGGAGGACCAGAUUGUCAUCUUUGCUGUUUGGGCAACUCAGCCAUUUCAGCCUUAGGGCUUCAGAGUGUCUGAGGUGAUGAGGAGCUGAAGUGAACCCCCAGCAUAGCACAGCUGCUUUACCAAAAAGUGGCCAGACCUACAUUUUAAGCAAGUCCCUGUUCUUGUUCCUCCUGAUUAGGCAAGAGUUUUUUCCACUUGCCUCCAGCCACCUCCUACAGGUGUGUUCAGAUUGGCAACAAGUUUGUACCUCAGUGGUACAGUACUCCCAGAGGAAGGGGCAGGCUAUCAUCUUUGCCUUUUCACAGCCUUCAUUGGUGAUACCUUCAGGCCCUGGAAAAUAUGAGGCAGUUAGGGACUGGAGUGCACCCCCAGCAUACCACAGCCCCCCUACGGAAAAGUGGCCAGACUGUUACGUGGGUGCCAGUUUCCAUAUCUUCUUGAUGGGCAGGUCUUCCCAUCCUGGGUCUCUAGCCAGCACCCCACUGGAGCUACCAAGCCAGUAGCAACUCAGCAAUUCCCUGGACAGAGCUUCCAGGAGCAACUGAAAUCCUCUAUGCCACUGCCUCUGCAGUGGAACUGUCCUUGCUACCCUUGGAAUAUCAAGGGAGCAAAGACUUUAAGUGCUGUAUUGACAUGUCCAACAAGUUGCAGUUGACCCAGUGAGCAAGCCAGUCCAUCUCCCAUGGGUCCCACACACUCUCCACUGUUCAUCACCCGACAGGGAACGCUGGCUUGGGCCCACAGCACAGACACUCCAUCCUGGGCUGAUCGCACUAAGUGAUUGCUAACUCACAUCUCUCUGGGGUGGAGCCCCUAGGAGAAAAGCCAAGUGGUAGAGCAGCAAGCCAGCUGAUGCGGAGCCCAAAGGGCAGGGACAGCUAUCUCUCUAGGCACCAUUUGCUCUUAUGAGACACUUUAUCCCAGCACUUUAGGAGUGCUGAGGUCAGACCAGCCACAUCUUAUGUGCAAGAUUGCCCAGCAGAGAUCAGGUCUGAGAGUUCCCCUCUUAAAAAAAGGGGACUUGCUUAAAAAAGAAGUCUGGCCACAUUUUUGUAGAGCAGCUGUGCUGUGUUGGGGCUUUAGUUUUGAGAGAGUUCUCCUCUGAGACCUGAUCUUUGCUGGGAA